CCCUGCCUCGGCGCUUUCGGUUUUGGCUGGGAUCAUCCGCGGCGGCCGGGCUCGUGGGGCGCCUGGAGUGAGGGUUCUGGUUCCCGCCGGCGAGGUGAGCCGCACCGCUGCGCGGGCCGACGACGGGGCCGGGCGCAGCCCCAGGUUCGGUGCCCCAGUGUUCAGUCGCGCUGUGGAGCGGCGGCUGCAGCGGCCCUAGGCCGGGCGAGGCAGCCCCGGAAAGGGCCUGCGGUGAACAGGCUGGGGCUCCGGGAAGGGACCGCUGGGUGGCGGGUCCCCGCGAAAUGCCGCGUCCAAGCUCUCCGCGCAUGGAAUGGCUGGGAGAGGUCUGAUGGUGGGCGCCGGGACCGCCCUCAGCGAGGCGCCUAGACUGCGCGGAGAGGAGCGGCACCGUCCCGGCUCCUACCGAGUUGGCGUCCGAGAUCAAUUCAGGUUGUUGAAGUUCCCCAGGGAGCCCCGACGCUAAUCCCAAGAUUCGGCGGGAAAGCGGAUCCCGAACCCAGGCCUAGGCUUCGCCUGUCUUCCAGGAGGGCUUCAGGGAAUUGCGAACCCUCUCCUACAUCGGGGUGGCUGCGCCUGACCACAGGAAUUAAAGGCUGGACUCGCCUGUCUUACCAAGUUGUCAGGUCGAGGAACCCGAUUGUAUGGUCUUAAGUCCUAUCGCCCAAGGUUUUCUGUGCGUAUGCGUGUCCGCACACCUGCAUAGCAGGCAUUUUUAAGGAUUGUUAAAAUGAGUCUUCGGAAGCAAACCCCUAGUGACUUCUUAAAGCAAAUCAUCGGACGACCAGUUGUGGUAAAAUUAAAUUCUGGAGUGGAUUAUCGAGGGGUCCUGGCUUGCCUGGAUGGCUACAUGAAUAUAGCCCUGGAGCAGACAGAAGAAUAUGUAAAUGGACAACUGAAGAAUAAGUAUGGGGAUGCAUUUAUCCGAGGAAACAAUGUGUUGUACAUCAGUACACAGAAGAGACGGAUGUGAAGACACCAAGAGAGCAACGCUUUUCAUAGUUGGAUAUAUUUUUUUAUGAAUUUUUUCUAAUUUUUGCUUCUUUUGUGAUACAAUUUGUCCUCUUUUUAUAAUAGUUGGUGAUUUUUCACUGACAUGUGAGUAAGAUAAAUGUAUACAAUUGUGGAUUUAAUUGUGAAAUGUUCUUUCACUUGUAAGUUUCAGUCAUUUUCUUUUACCUCGUUGUCAGUGUACAGAAUGCUAAAAUAAUUAAAAAAAGACAAAAUAUACCUCUUCCUACAAGAUUAUUUAACUUAAGUUUCGAGAAGUGUCAUUUCAUUUGACUUGCUUUUCUUAUCCAGCUAAAAUGAUGCAUAUAUUUUAUAUAUUGUAUGGACAUAUAAUUAAAACAUUUUGGAGGAAUCCUCCUUUAUUGCAUCCUUUUCUGUUCAUACAGAAUCCUUGCGUGAAUAUGUUCUACAAAGGCAUCCAGUUUCAGUCUGAAGCUACAAAAAGGGGCCACAGGAUCAGAAGUUCAGCCACUGAUUGAGUCACCUAAAUAAAAAACAGAAUUGGAAAGCCAAGAGUGCCACUUGCACAUAAGGAGUGGGAAUUCGAACUGAGGUGCUGGAGAAAUCCUAAAGAUGAACAAGAUUUCAGUGAGGAGAAAGCCCUCCUGUCAGUGGUCCCCCUGCAUCUCCUUAUGCAAUUAGACUUUUUAGGUUUCCCUGCUCCCUUUCAGGAGCAUUGGCAUCAACGUUAUUCUCUCAGUUUAUGAACACAGUAGGGGAGGGGCCAUUCCUGUACAUCUCUCACAGUCAGAUUAAAGCAAAGCCUAGAGUUUGUAAACAUAAUUCAGGUUCUAAUUGCCGAGCUGAGAUUGGGAAAGAAUUUUUCCUAACUCUGGUCUAGCAAGUGGCUGUAGGGAGGCCUUUCUCAAAAAUCAGCUGUAUUUGCCUUUGACAUUGUCCAGGAGCAGAGCACCAGGCUUUAUGUUGCUUGGCACAAGGCAGCUCCUCUGGUUAUGUGACUCCUGCUGAGAGGAUUUUCACAAUUUAUUAAUGAGCUUUCCACAACCCUGCUUUAUUCUCCAAACAGUUUUACGCUGUCUCUAGGAACAACAAAUAUAUCUGGGCACUGUGGUUGAAUGAAUACCAGACAAUUGUGUGAAUGUUGUAUUGGACUUCCUCUUCCCUCCCUUCCCAAUCUAAAUAGCAUUCCUAUUUCAGGAGCCGAUGGUGUGAUUCGAAACAACUGCUUGGUUGAAGGAUGGGGGGCAGGAUCGAGAAGGAGAGAGGGAAGGGGCAGUGCUGAUUCUGGAGAGGUGUAUGUAGUGUUUUGUCUUGGUUUAUUUUAAAGAUCAGAGAGUAAUUGGAAACAAUUAUUUUUUAAUUAAUAACUUGGGAAAGGUGAACAGAAGCAUUUCACAGGGUUUUACCGUGUGCACACUGAAAAUAAAACACUUUAUGCUAUGCUUCAAUAAUUUAUCACUUCUUGACAGGGGCUUGGAAAAGGUCCAGUAUGUAAGUACAAAUCACCAAUUUGCUCUUUUAUAAAUGAGUUCUUUUAAGGAGAAAAUGGAUGGCUCUCCAAGUGGAGCAUACAUGUUCUCAUUUGUUUUGUAGAAUAUGUGGGGCUGCAGGUUAUUGUGUCCCUUCAUUCACUUAUAUCAGCCACCUCUAAAAGCAAUUCCAUUGUAGUCUCCCACUAAUCUGUAGCGUCCUGUUUUUUCUAACUUCUUCCCUGACCUCGCCUUUGAUAUAUAAGUCUUUAUUUUCCCCUUGCCAUCUCUCUAGUUUAAUAGCUCUACAGUGGAGUACUGUUUUCAACCAUGGAACUACUUUUAAUCAAGAUCAACUUUGGGAAGUGCUGCCAUUUUUAUGGUAAUAAAGGACUGUAUUAUGCACUUGAA